UCAAUUAUGCGGGCCACAGCCAGUCAUUAAAAAAAUAAGCAGAAUGCUUUUCUCAGUGACAGGAAGCAUCCUCCCCUACGGUGGGUGUGAGGAGCUUGUUCUCCUUGGCAAGUGCCUCCUCAGCCCUGGCCCCUGGCUUCCAUGCCACGGCCUGUGCCCAGCUCUCCAGUCUCAUUCUCCUCUCCUGGGGCAUUUAGCUUGAAGGGUUCCUUGUGGCCCAGACCCCCAAGGUCCCAGCACCAAGCCCUUCAUUCUUCUCUGCCUCCCUCCAUAGGCAGGGCCUGGGCAGACAGAGCAGCCCUGGACCAACCACAUUUACUGGGACCAAGAGGGUGGAGUCAAGGAAGGAAGGAACACAGAUCUUGGGGCUUGGGUUGGCUUCCUGGGAGACGUUUGAUUUGCUCAUUAGUUCCUCCCUCUCUUUCCUUCCUCCCUCCCUCCCUUCCUUCCUUCCUUCUUUCCUUCCCUUCUCUUCCUUCCUUUUCAAUACAUUGAGCCCUUGUGAUGUGGCUGGCAUCAUGCUGGGCCCUGGGAAUAUAAUGAAUGAGGCUCGUUCUUUGCUCCUAAGUUGCCUAUACCAGGUGAUACAGACAGACAAGCAAAAAGGUCUCUUCCCUAAAAGCUUUUAAAAAAUCCUGAUGCUAGUCCCAGCAGCAGAUCUUUGCUUUAGGGUGGGCCUGGAAAUUGGUAUAUUUGAAAAGCUUCCUAGGUGACUCCAGCUUGCAGCUCUGGUUAUGAGCCCCAGAUGGAGGGGCAGUGCCCUGCCAUGGAUAUGGGCCUGGAGCUGAGAGCCUGCCCAGGGUACUUGAGUCUGGGCUGUAUUCCUUCCCACUGAGUGACCUUGGCUGUGCCUCUUUAACUCUCUGUGACUUGGUUCCUUCAUUUGUAAAACAGAGUGCUAUCUUAGGCAGCUGGAAGAAUUCCUUGAGCUGAUGGCACAUGGCGGGUGCUCAGCAAGCAUUGUCUAUUGUUAUCAAGCACUAACAAAGGUGCACUGCAGCAUGUAGGAAAGGCACCUCACCUUUUCUGUAGAAAGGAUGGGGCAGAAGAGUGAGGAGUUAGCUGGGCAAAGGGACUGGGGAGAUGAGGGAAUGGGAGAAUAGGAAUCGUGGAUUGAGGGAGCUGGAGGAGGUGGCCGGCUCUUCAAGAACAAGAGAACAGCUUGUGCCAAGGCUGGGAGGUAGAGCUGGAUAUGACUGGUGGGCCAGCGGCGAAGUGCAGAGUGGGCGGGAAGAGGCUGGGGAGGCCCACCCGAGUGUGGCUGAAAGCUCUUUGAGGACUAGGGGCUGGGGUGGGGACAGCCAUGCUAUGACAGCCUCUCCUGUUCCAGCCCUGCAGCUGGUGAGCAGUAAGAGGGACUUGGUUCUGGUGAAGGAGGCGCUGAGCUGGUACGACGCCCAGCAGCACUGCCGGCUGCACUACACAGACCUCGCUGACCUGCAGCCAAGUGGCCUGUGGAAGCUCUACUCCCUCAUGACCAGCACCCCGGCUUGGAUUGGCCUCUUCUUCGACGCAAGCACUUCUGGCCUGAGAUGGUCCAGCGGCUCCACCUUCACAGCCCUGGAGUGGGGCCAGAAGCUACCUGAAUUUGGGGUGGGCUUCUGUGCCACGCUGUACACUUGGCUGAAAUUACCCAGCAUAGGGGCUGCCUCCUGCACAGCCCAGAAGCCCUUCCUCUGCUACUGUGACCCUGACGUCGGGCACCUCAUCUCCACGAAGCCCUCUCUCAGCCUGACCACCUCUCCAAAGCCAGCUGUGGUCCAGAUCAGUGGUCAGACCUUCAUGCGAUUUGACCAAGUGAUGACAUGGUCCUCGGCCCUGCUGUACUGCCGCAGCCACCACACGGAUCUGGCCGACCUGCAGAUGGUGACGGAUGAGACAGGCAAGGAGGCCUUGAGAUCCAUCAUGAGUGAGACUGAAGCCUGGAUUGGCCUCUACCUCAAUGCAAACUCCGGAUCUCUGAGCUGGUCCAGUGACCUGGGGGCCAGCAUCCCCUCCUGGCUGCAGGUGCCGAUGAUGGUGAGAGGACUGUGCACAGCUCUUGGCAUCUAUAUGACCUACUCCCCAAAAGUGUACUCAGUGAACUGCUCUUCCCUGCUGCCCUUCUUCUGCUUCUAUGCUGUGGCCAGUGUAGGGAGUGGCACUGAUAGAAGAGAUACAGCUGCUGCCACGGAGGCCCAACAUCUGAGUUCAGAAUCUAAAGAAAAAACAUCAGCACAAAAAUCAGGGCACCCUUUUGGAAUCUUGAAAGCAGACUUUACCAUCUCAACUCUGAUGGACCCAGAAGAGAUGAAAGACCAAUUUCUGAGACAGAUCCAGGAAGUCUUAAAGCUUACAUUAGGUCACGAACAAUUUAGACUGAAAUGGGUCAGCUUCGAAGUGAACAAAAAAUAGCACAAUUCUUGGAUAUGCAGUUUCUGUUUCAUGCAAUCUUCUCUGGAUUUUGAGUAAAUUUUAAUUUUUUAAUCCCUAGUAGAACAAGAUUAGGAAGAACUCGACAUGUGCCAAAAAGCACAGACCUACAACUAACACAAAACAAGACUACACAUGAAACCUGCAUCCCUGGAUUUUACAGAAUGAAACAGGGAUGCAGGAGAAGAUGGGUGUAUUUGGGAACAAUCAUGUUGGGAAUGACAAAUGAACUUCUAUUAAGAAAUUAAAAUAAAAAACCUGAACCAAACAUCAAAAAUCCUGAAAACAAACCCCAUUAAUCUAACUGGAAAAUUACAAGAGGAUGGUAGUGGUCUAGGAAGCUAAGUGGGGCUACAUUUCCUAAUAAACCAGAUGAAACUUUCUUUACCUGUCACAAGUUAUUAAAGAGAUUUCAAAUUCUGCAGAAUUCGAAAGUAACAGUUUUAUCACAAUACAUGCUAAUGCUAGUUAUUUUUCCUAAAUUGAAAUCUUAUUACAUGGAAGUUGGGAAAUUCUAGGACAGACUGUUCUUAAUGUUAAAAUAUAUUUUUAGAAGAAUAUUCCGGCAUACAUUUCCUUUCUUGUUUCUCUUCAAGUGUCCUAGUCACCCAGGUGCAUGCUAGAAGACAGCAAUAUGUCAAAUAUAGUAGCAACUUUAGUCUGAAAUGUUUAAAGUUAAAGUUUAUUUGUAUUCUUUGUAGGAAUAUCAAUAAAAGACCUCAAAC